CCCAGCCCCAGUUACAGAUUAUCUAUCUGGACAAGGACAGGAGGCUCCCAGGAGUGGGGGAACUUGGAUGUUGGCAGAAGUGGGCUGGUCUAAGGUUCCCCACCUUCCUUGUUCCACCUCCAGCCUCUGGGGAAGUAGGUACCUGCCUGGGAGAGUGACAUCUCAGCUCAUGCCCCACGCCCCAGUGUGAUUUGUGGCUGGCCUGUCUGUAUCUGUAAUAGUGAUAGCUUGGUCUAAAAGGAGACCCUGGGAACAGACAGAGUGGGCCGGCCAGGAGCCUGACAGCACAGCCCUAGCCUGGUCGCAGAUGUCACCUGACAACUUUCCAUUUGCAAAUCCUCCUUCCUCCUCGGACAUCCGGACACCCCAUUGCCCCCUCUCAGAGCCCAGGUCUCUGGUUUCUGCCUGUGAUUCUGGGCUGUAGCCCCUUUAGAAACUCAGGUGUCCUGGUCACCUCCUACCCCCAGGGCUGACUAGCCUUCAGCUUGGCAGUCCCUGCCCCUGGGGCCCUAGUAACCAGAGCCAGGCUCCAGCCGGCUUUUCCGGUUAGAGGUUGGAGGUGGUGCCCAGAGUGCCCCUGGAGGGGGUGGAGGGGCCUACGCCCCGGAAGUCCUGAGCCUUGGAACGCUUUCAGGCCUGGUGGCGGUGGGAGCCGGGGCUGGCCCAGACGCUGAGUGUCUGCAGUCAGGGAGCAUCGAGGCAGAUGUUUUCAGGCCUUGGUGUCAGGGGUGGGAGAGGGAUGCCUCGUUUUGGGGAGGGGGCCACCCGAGGAGGCUGGAGGGCGGCGGCCCUGUGGACUAUCCCUCAUGUGCUCUUCGAGGCAGCAUGAUCCCAGUGGCCGAGUUCAAGCAGUUCACGGAACAGCAGCCUGCGUUCAAGGUGCUCAAACCCUGGUGGGACGUGCUGGCCGAGUACCUCACCGUGGCCAUGCUCAUGAUUGGGGUCUUUGGCUGCACCCUCCAGGUGACACAGGACAAGAUCAUCUGUCUACCCAAUCAUGAGCUCCAGGAGAACUUAUCAGAGGCCCCGUGCCAGCAAUUGCUGCCUCGGGGGAUCCCUGAGCAGAUUGGGGCCCUGCAGGAGGUUAAAGGCCUUAAGAACAAUUUGGACCUGCAGCAAUACAGCUUUAUUAACCAGCUGUGUUAUGAGACGGCCCUGCACUGGUAUGCCAAGUACUUCCCUUACCUCGUGGUCAUUCACACACUCAUCUUCAUGGUCUGCACCAGUUUCUGGUUCAAGUUCCCUGGCACCAGCUCCAAGAUUGAACACUUCAUCUCCAUCCUGGGCAAGUGUUUCGACUCUCCAUGGACCACCAGGGCCCUAUCCGAGGUCUCCGGGGAGAACCAGAAGGGCCCAGCAGCCACCGAACGGGCUGCGGCCACCAUAGUGGCCAUGGCAGGGACCGGGCCGGGGAAGGCAGGGGAGGGUGAGAAGGAGAAAGUGCUGGCGGAACCGGAGAAGGUGGUGACCGAGCCUCCAGUUGUCACCCUGUUGGACAAGAAGGAGGGUGAGCAAGCCAAAGCCCUGUUUGAGAAGGUGAAGAAGUUCCGCAUGCACGUGGAAGAGGGCGACAUCCUGUACACCAUGUACAUCCGACAGACGGUGCUGAAAGUGUGUAAGUUCCUGGCCAUCCUGGUCUACAACCUGGUCUAUGUGGAGAAGAUCAGUUUCCUGGUGGCCUGUAGGGUGGAGACGUCAGAGGUCACGGGCUACGCCAGCUUCUGCUGCAACCACACCAAGGCCCACCUCUUCUCCAAGCUGGCCUUCUGUUACAUCUCCUUUGUGUGCAUCUACGGACUUACCUGCAUCUACACGCUCUACUGGCUCUUCCACCGGCCCCUCAAGGAGUACUCCUUCCGUUCCGUGCGGGAGGAGACUGGCAUGGGGGACAUUCCUGACGUCAAGAAUGACUUCGCCUUCAUGCUGCACCUCAUCGAUCAGUACGACUCCCUCUACUCCAAGCGCUUCGCCGUCUUCCUGUCCGAGGUCAGCGAAAGCCGUCUAAAGCAGCUCAAUCUCAACCACGAGUGGACGCCCGAGAAGCUUCGACAGAAGCUGCAGCGCAAUGCCGCGGGCCGGCUGGAGCUGGCCCUCUGCAUGCUGCCGGGUCUGCCCGACACCGUCUUUGAGCUCAGUGAGGUGGAGUCACUCAGGCUGGAGGCCAUCUGCGAUAUCACCUUCCCCCCGGGGCUGUCACAGCUGGUGCACUUGCAGGAGCUCAGCUUGCUCCACUCGCCCGCCAGGCUACCCUUCUCCUUGCAGGUCUUCCUGCGGGACCACCUGAAGGUGAUGCGCGUCAAAUGCGAGGAGCUCCGCGAGGUGCCGCUUUGGGUGUUUGGGCUGCGGGGCUUGGAGGAGCUGCACCUGGAGGGGCUUUUCCCCCAGGAGCUAGCUCGGGCAGCCACCCUGGAGAGCCUCCGGGAGCUGAAGCAGCUCAAGGUGUUGUCCCUCCGGAGCAACGCCGGGAAGGUGCCAGCCAGUGUGACCGACGUUGCUGGCCACCUGCAGAGGCUCAGCCUGCACAACGAUGGGGCCCGUCUGGUUGCCCUGAACAGCCUCAAGAAGCUGGCGGCAUUGCGGGAGCUGGAGCUGGUGGCCUGCGGGCUGGAGCGCAUCCCCCAUGCAGUGUUCAGCCUGGGUGCGCUGCAGGAACUUGACCUCAAGGACAACCACCUGCGCUCCAUCGAGGAAAUCCUCAGCUUCCAGCACUGCCGGAAGCUGGUCACGCUCAGGCUGUGGCACAACCAGAUCGCCUACGUCCCUGAGCACGUGCGGAAGCUCAGGAGCCUGGAGCAGCUCUACCUCAGCUACAACAAGCUGGAGACCCUGCCCUCCCAGCUCGGCCUGUGCUCAGGCCUCCGUCUGCUGGAUGUGUCCCACAAUGGGCUACACUCCCUGCCACCCGAGGUGGGCCUCCUGCAGAACCUACAGCACCUGGCCCUCUCCUACAAUGCCCUGGAGGCCCUGCCCGAAGAGCUCUUCUUCUGCCGCAAGCUGCGGACGUUGCUUCUGGGCGACAACCAGCUGAGCCAGCUCUCGCCCCACGUGGGUGCCCUCAGAGCCCUCAGCCGCCUGGAGCUCAAAGGCAACCGCUUAGAGGCGCUGCCAGAAGAACUUGGCAACUGUGGGGGGCUCAAGAAGGCGGGGCUCCUGGUGGAAGACACGCUUUACCAGGGUCUGCCGGCAGAAGUGCGGGACAAGAUGGAGGAGGAAUGAAGCUGGGGUGGGGCCGUUUUAGGUAGAGCCUUAAAAAUGCUUCUGCCCUGGAAUCUCAACCAUUGUCUUCCAAGAUAGGAAGCCAAGUGGGUCCAGGCCAGGAGAUGGGGGGGGCGGGGGCAGCUGUGUCAUCUUUCUGGGGCCCAGGAGGAUCUGGGCUGGUUUGUCUGGGGAGACAGACAGGAUGUUGUGGAGCUGGGGUGGAACCUGGUAUGGAGGGAUUAACUCAGUCAUGGCAUUCUCCGACCAAAACCACACCUGUGUCUCUGGCAGGCUGGCUGGCCUUGCUCCCAUCCCUAGAACUGCUGCCUCUCCCUGGAUAUUCCAGCUCAAUUAGUGCCACAUAUGGGGGAAACGACACAUCCCAGUGGGAUUUCCAACACUCCCCCUCCCCAUGCAACAAAGCAACUUACUUCUGGAGUUCUCUCCCAAGGAGAGGACACAGACACAGUUGUUUGCUGUGUUAUAUGUUAGCUCCGAACAAUGGUUCUCAUUUGGCUAAGCAUCAAAAUCACCUAGGGAGUCGGUGCAAAACAAAAUAUCCCAGUCCCCUCCCCUGAAACACUGACUCAGGAGGUUUGGUUGGGGGCCAGGAGUCUGUUCCUAAAUAUUCCAGGUAGUUCUGGUGCAGGUAAGUGGCCCUGAGACAGUAUGUUGGGAAAUGCUGACGUAAAGGUAUCAGGGCCGGGCGCUGUGGCUCAUGACUAUAAUCCCAGCUGUUUGAGAGGCCAAUGCAGGAGGAUGGUUGAGCUCAGGAGUUCGAGAUCAGCCUGGGUAACAUAGCGAGACCCCACCUCUGCCAAAAAAAAAAAAAAUAGGGUAUCCAAAUAUCUAGAUUCUGAUCCCUUUUGAGGUCCUAGACCCUUUGAGAAACUGAUGAAGCCAGGCACCUCCUUCCUCAGGAAAAUGCUGGUGUACAAAUACACACAAAGCUCUUCAGGCAGCUGAUAGAUUUCCCCCAGAGAGCUAUUCAAGGACUUCCUAAGGUGGGUGGACUGCAGGGUUAGGACACCUGCUAUAGAGGUGACAUUUUUCCAAGGACAAGCAGGGACUUUGGUCUUGACUGUUCUCUGGGUGCUUAAUAAAUAAUACUAAUUAUGCAA